GGGGCACCCGGAAGCGCGCGUGGACCUGGCGCACCGAGCCGGGCGGGCGGAGGGGCGGUUGGGACGGCGCGGGGAGGCGGGCGCGCCGCCCGGGCCGCGGCGGGCUGUGGUCACAGGUGGGCGGCUGCGGCGAGGGAGCGGCCGAGCGGAGCCCGGGUCCCGGAGACUCCUGCCGUCACGCCCGGGGCUCCGCGUAGCAGAGAUCGGGAGACGCGUCUGUGCCUCCGGGGAAGCCGACCCAUCUCCCCUCCGCCUCUUUGGCUGCAGUUGCACCUCCGGCCAGAGGGCAGCCCCGAGGCUGAGUUCCCACCAGCGCCCAGGCUUGGAGCGGAGACCGCUCGGCCCUCCCAGCCUGCACCCGCAGGUGAGCGCAACCGCCCGCGCCCCGGCUGUCCCGGACGCGUGGUCGGCUGUCGCCAUAGGAACGGCUGGUGCCCAGACGGCGCCUGCCCAGGCUGGGAAGGGGCGGUGAAGGCAGCUCAGACCUCCAAGAACCCUGGAGCCCCCUGUGUGGCCAGGCGGAGCCACAGAAGCCUGAUGAAAACGGGACCCCCUCCCCCUCUCUCUUCUCAUUUUUGAUUGCUCAGGCGUUGGAGGUUAAGCAGAGAGAGAGAGGCGUGGACCUAUUUACGAGAUGUAAGUUGUGUUCUUUCCACCUUUACCUUCUGAGGGCUUCUUACGCCUCAUGGUGACAGGUGCAAAUCAUGACACAGAAGGGCAGUAUGAAGCCUGUGAAGAAAAAGAAAACCGAAGAACCUGAAUUGGAGCCCCUGUGCUGCUGCGAGUACAUAGAUCGGAAUGGGGAAAAGAACCACGUGGCUACUUGUUUGUGUGAUUGUCAAGAUCUGGAUGAAGGGUGUGAUCGAUGGAUUACAUGUAAAUCUUUACAGCCAGAGACUUGUGAAAGAAUCAUGGAUACAAUUUCUGAUCGCCUCCGAAUUCCUUGGCUUAGGGGAGCCAAAAAAGUGAACAUCAGCAUCAUCCCUCCGCUUGUCCUGCUGCCUGUCUUCCUUCAUGUGGCUUCCUGGCAUUUCCUCCUGGGGGUGGUGGUUUUGACCUCCCUUCCUGUGCUGGCACUGUGGUACUACUACCUCACUCACAGAAGGAAAGAACAGACCCUGUUUUUCCUGAGCCUUGGACUGUUCUCUCUGGGCUACAUGUACUAUGUGUUCCUGCAGGAAGUGGUCCCCAAAGGGCGUGUGGGUCCCGUUCAGCUGGCGGUUCUUACCUGCGGGUUAUUUCUGAUACUCUUAGCCUUGCACAGAGCCAAGAAGAAUCCAGGCUACCUCAGCAAUCCAGCAAGCGGUGACAGAUCUCUAAGCAGCAGCCAGCUGGAGUGCCUGAGCAGAAAAGGGCAGGAGAAGACCAAAGGGUUCCCUGGGGCAGACAUGUCGGGCAGUCUCAACAAUCGCACAACAAAGGAUGACCCCAAGGGCUCUUCCAAGAUGCCAGCUGGAAGCCCCACCAAAGCGAAGGAGGACUGGUGUGCCAAGUGCCAGCUGGUGCGACCAGCCCGGGCAUGGCACUGCCGGAUAUGUGGCAUCUGUGUGAGGAGAAUGGAUCAUCAUUGUGUCUGCUGCGUUGGAGAAUCAAAUCAUCAAGCAUUUAUACUUGCCCUUUUGAUCUUCUUGCUCACCUCGGUGUAUGGGAUCACACUGACCUUGGACACCAUUUGUAGAGACAGAAGUGUCUUCACAGCUCUUUUCUAUUGUCCUGGAGUUUAUGCAAAUUACAGCUCGGCUCUGUCCUUCACCUGCGUGUGGUACUCUGUGAUCAUCACAGCAGGCAUGGCCUACAUCUUCCUGAUCCAGCUGAUCAACAUCAGCUACAAUGUGACUGAGCGGGAAGUCCAGCAGGCCCUCCGACAGAAGACUGGGCGCCGGCUCCUCUGCGGGCUCAUCGUGGACACAGGCCAGUACAAUAGGGGCUUCCUGCGGAACUGGCACCAGUUCUCCACCCUGGGCACACGUGCAUUCCACCACCCUGCCGAGGACAUUGUCUGAAGUGCCUUCUAUGUGGCUCUCUGAGGGAUGAUGGCUCCUCCUUCCGUCUCCCUUCCAUUUUACACUUCAGUGUCCAUUUCUAUCCCCAGUUUCUUAAAGGCAUUAUAGGGCCAUGCUCAGGUUUAGAGACUGGAGUGGGAAGAAGUUAAUUUUUCUGACGCCACAACUUAAGAGACUUUUAUACUGAGGCAGUAAAAGUAGAGCCAUUCCUUUCCAGUCACCUUUUUAAUUGACUCAGUUGCCUGAACUUGAGAAGGAUGUGGAUUGCUAAUGCACAAAUUGAUAGAAGCAAUUCCCAUCCAUUAGUAUGGAGGAAAGAGUGUUGGAUUAGGAUAGUUUCUAGUCCCUCUUUCGAUUCUUAAUAGCCAUGUGACCCCUAGCUGAGUCACUUUCCCAAGUCUCAGGGUCAUCUGCAAAGUGGGGUACUGAUGCCUGCCCUGGCUACCUCACAGAGCCGUCAUGAGGGUCACGUGAGGGAAGAUGGAUGUGGAAAGCACUAAAAAACAACUCAAGAGCCAUGGAAAUACAAAGUAUUAGGAAAAUAUUAUGAUGGAAGAAAAACGUUUAUAGUCUAGAAUAUUGAAGCCAAUAUUAUUAGGGUAAUCAGUUUUCAGCAUAUACCUUGUUGUACAGUUAUGAGAAUUUCUCCUUCUUAUUAGACAUGAACUACUCAAACAGAGAAGAUGACCAGAUGGAUUGAUGCUAAGUUGUCUCAUCUUGAAAAGACAGUUGACAACAGUUAUAAAGAUAAUUAUUGCUAGUGUAAUGUAGUGUGGCCAUGAGUUUAGGUGAUGAGUUCUUCUAUUUAUAUUUUAUAAAUUCUGCUUGGGUUUCUUAUAAAUAACUCCAACAGGCAUUCAUGUGUUUUUCCUCUUCCCAUGUUUCACCAGGUAAGGUGCUAGCACACUUGUGACUGUGGCUGGAAGAGGAGAACAGACACUCCUGUGGGGAUGCUUUACUCUCUUUUCUGGUAGGAAGGCUGAGUAACAUCACGGGCUCGAUUAUUUUCUUCAUGUAUUUCAAAUGCUGUCAGUUAUAGCACUAAAUUGUGAAAAUCAGCCUUCUGGCAUUCACAUUAUUCUGGUAUGAACUUUGAGGAGUUGAGUGACAUCUUCCCACUUAACUUGCACAUUAAUUCUCAAUUACCCCUCCCUAAAUAACAGUAUCUCACUAAGAGAGAAGAAACAGGGUAUAUGUGGUUUCCACUAUUAAUGGAUUACUGUUCUUCCCUGGCUCUUCCGACAAUAACAAGUUGUUUCUUUAAUCAUAUCUUAAAACCGAAAAUGUAUAAAAGAUUAAAUAUUUAUGUACAAUGGGUUGUUCUACUAUAGAAUUAAGAUGAGGGAAUUUCAGAUGAGGAAAAUACCCUUUUGAAAUGUUAGUUUUGAACAUGUACUGUUGUGCAAUCCCAAAGAUAAUUCAUGACUCCUUAAAUUUGCCUUGGCUUAUAGCUUAAUAUAGGGAAAAUAUUGCCAGCGUUUUCAGUCAUUCUGUGCAUGCUGCUUUAAGCAAGAGAUUUAUAUUUGUUGAGAGGAAAUAUUGCUACUUCCUGCACUUCCACCCUCUGCAGCCAGCACCGUCCCUACUGUUGCCAUUAAUUGGAGCUGUCCUUAAGAUGGUCACCAUAUUCUUAUUCAGGCUGUUGUCAUUUUCCCCAGAGAUGGUUUGUUUAACGAAUGAUAGGCUCUGUGCCUGGGGAUGUUAGCAGACUCUGGGGUUUGUACAGUGAUGCCUUCUCCCUGGCCCAGAGCUGAAUAUUCAUCUAGAAUUAAAGUUGGAUUUGAUAUAACAAAUUUCUUUCUAUACAGGUUUUACAUAAGAGAGACAGUAAUAAUGUCAAGGAUAGCCUGUGUGGGCAGAAAUUGGUAGUCGUGCUUUUGAAUGUCAGCUGUAGAGCCAACUCUGAUUAUCUAGCCAUUGAUCAUACAAAUUGAUAGAAACAUUAGUCAGUAAUUUUAGCUUCUUGCCAAAUUGUUCACAACAUCUAAAUGUAAUGUGAUGUGAUGAAGAUAAGUAGUACAAAGAGACCAAAAUAAUUUGGGAGAAUUAGGAAUGAUGACAAUUUUUUUUAACAACUUACCUCUAAUAGGGUUACUUGGAUGAGCCAACUCCGCUUCCUUCCCAUGGAUAGGAAGGGACUCUGUGUAUUAUUCAGGUUUAUUGGCACGAAGAUACUUGUUUUAAGUUCCUUGAGAACCCAUGAUGGACAGUUGACAGAAUGCUUAAACCUGUCAAAAGAUGAGUGAUCUUGUGUGGGAAAAGCCUUCCCAGGCGUCUGUACCGAAAGGAGCAGCAAACAAGGGGCUAAUCCAUGAGCAGUGUUCUGUAGGCUCUGUGACAUCUUUGGUUUAUAGGAUUUUGGAGCCUUUUAUGAUCUGGAACUAUUUGAGGGGUUUCAUUAUAGGCCUUGGUUCUCUCCAGGGGCCAGAUGAGUUUAUUGUGGAAUCUUUGAAAGGACAAGGCCUCUGUGAAUGAAUCAGUCCCAGGGAAGCAUUUGGUGGUGGCGGCAGUGGAGGAUUGCCCGGUGAACCUAUAAAUCAGCAGUCUCUUGGGCAGAGGAGCAAGCCCCUCGAACAUGAUUUCAAACAAGCAGGUCCUCUUCUCUCAUCUCACGUCCUUAGUCUCUGUUAAUGAACAUACUGGAUGUGGAGUUUAAUAAAUUACCUACUAUCAUCUGGCCACUUAGAUUAUUAUCACACCACUGUGGACUGUUCCUGGGGGGAGAAGAACAGACCGAUUUGAAAGAUUCAAGGGAGAAAGAUUAAGGAUCAGGAUUGCAUGAAAGAAGAAAAUCCUUCAAUAUUUAAAAUGUUUCUUACAAUACCCACGGAGCACUUUUAUGGUUCCAGCCGAGCGUUCCUGAAAUGAACUGACCAUUAACAGCGCCUCUUUGAUAGGUUACCCUGAUGCUGCUAAAGUAAAGCCUUAAGUGUGUUUUUGGGACAACGUGCUGCUUAUUCCACCUCAGCCACAUAUGUGUUUGUGUUUAGGAUAUUGUAAAUCUUUGCUAAGUAGUGUUUUCCUUGGUGAAUGAAGUCAUUGUUGUCUUCAAGUGUACCAUCUGCCUAGCAAAAAAUUGCUACAAACUUUCUCUUAUGCAAUAGUCCUUGGUACUUCUAAUAUUUUUAGCAAGAGACAAUUUUCUGUACUAGAAUCUUCCACUGCCAGAAAACACAGUGCCAGUAAGGUUCUACAUACCACUGACCAUCUGCUUAAUAGACAUGUAUUUCCUUUGAGUAGGACAUUAGCUUUUGAUUAUAAAGCUCAACUAGUAUAAGCAAAAAUAUAACAUCUAGAAGCACAGUUUUAGCCAGGAUGUUUAAAAAUUACAGUUUUGUGAGACUUAAGGGUCUUUUUAACCUAGGUAAGUUUAUAUGACCUAACUUAAUUGUAGCCAUAUUCUGGUACCUUCCAUUUUGAAAAGUAGAGGUUGCUUAAGCAAGCAAUGGAUAAUAAGAGACUUUUCCUGAGGCACCUGUUUGGAAUCUGGUUUUCUCAGCGGCAGCUUGACAUGUGCACCCUUUUGUAUUAAACACUGCAAGGGUGAUGCAGGGGAGCAGGAAAGCCAUCCUAAACUCACUACUGAGUACGAUUCAGUAUGUUCCUGUGGAUGUCUGCUGUGACUAAUAUAAAUUUCUUGCAGAAUCAGCUACACUUAAUUAUGUUGCUGAUAGACAAGCAUCCACGCUUCAGCUGGCACUAAGUGUUUUCAUUGUAGGAUCAGCAGCAGGUUAAAGACUGAACGGUUAGUGAAGACAAAUGUCUUAAGAGGCUGCGAUGUCUAGGUUGGGCUUGUGACUUCUUAGUGGCCUAGCCUUCUUGAUGGCACCUUGAAAGUGAACUUCUAGAAAUCUACAUUUAAAAGGCAAAGCUUUAAAAGCAGAGCUAGUCUAUUCUAGUUACUGAUGCAACUAAAAUUCUGUAUUUCUUAAGAUGGAGCCACUGACGAGAUGUCACAGUAUAGAGCCUGCAGUCUCAACUCAUUGUGAUCCUAAUGGUCUGGGUGAUUGGAUGGUUUGAGUUGUUAGGGAUUUUGAGUUUUUCAUUUUAUUGCAUAUCUGGGUUGGAUGUUAGACUAAAGGAAACCCAGGAAUAUUUACCUGGUGUUACAUUUAAUAUUUAAUGUAACUGGUCUAGCAACAUUAAGGGGGAUUUCUGAAGCCAACUCCGGAGGCUGUGGGCUGCACAUUUUGCACUGUUUUUAUAUACUUGUAUUCAUAUCCUCUUAUCACCUCAGACUCAGACACAAGGCCUUUUACAUGGAAAUUUUACAAAUUACUUCCAUUUAUGUAAAAUAACGUCCUGUGACCAAGUUGUUUAAAUGGAAAAUAAAGUGCUUUCUUUAAGGAAAAUAGCUGGUGUUUCUUGGAGUGUCUCCUGAAGUCUUCUGAUUUCUGAAAACCCUGCAUUAUACCUGUGCUGCCUCUGUGGCUCCCUCAAUGUCUCUAUCCUGUGGCCCUGUCCCUAGCCCUAAACUGUUAUGUUCCCGGUGGCAAUUUCUCCAGUUUUGUGGGUCAGGGAUACUGCUUGUUGGGGCAUUAUGUUAACAGUAACAUUUUGAAACAUACUUUCAUGAUAGUCCAGCAAAAAACAGCAUCAAAACUAUUUCCAUUGUAUCUCUUUAGAAGGCUCUGUAUUCGGUAAAAAGUCUAGCUGGCGCCAUUGGAAUAUGGGCUGCUAAAGACUCAAUUUCUAGUUGAUGUUUGAGGUGAGGCAAAAAUAAAGCUAAGGUAGAAAACUUAA